GUUUCCGGCGGUCGCGCGCUCUUUUCUCGGGACGGGAGAGGCCGUGUAGCGUCGCCGUUACUCCGAGGAGAUACCAGUCGGUAGAGGAGAAGUCGAGGUUAGAGGGAACUGGGAGGCACUUUGCUGUCUGCAAUCGAAGUUGAGAGGCCCAGUAUUUAGGCGACAGUGAAUUUAUUACUCUGAAGAGGGUUCUGCACAUAUUUCCAAAUUAUAUUGGUGGUCAUCAGAAGUAGGUGAUAGGAAGAAAUACUUCUCAAGGGUGCAAAAAUGCAGAGUAAUAAAACUUUUAACUUGGAGAAGCAAAACCAUACUCCAAGAAAGCAUCAUCAACAUCACCACCAGCAGCAGCACCACCAGCAGCAACAGCAGCAGCCGCCACCACCGCCAAUACCUGCAAAUGGGCAACAGGCCAGCAGCCAAAAUGAAGGCUUGACUAUUGACCUGAAGAAUUUUAGAAAACCAGGAGAGAAGACCUUCACCCAACGAAGCCGUCUUUUUGUGGGAAAUCUUCCUCCCGACAUCACUGAGGAAGAAAUGAGGAAACUAUUUGAGAAAUAUGGAAAGGCAGGCGAAGUCUUCAUUCAUAAGGAUAAAGGAUUUGGCUUUAUCCGCUUGGAAACCCGAACCCUAGCGGAGAUUGCCAAAGUGGAGCUGGACAAUAUGCCACUCCGUGGAAAGCAGCUGCGUGUGCGCUUUGCCUGCCAUAGUGCAUCCCUUACAGUUCGAAACCUUCCUCAGUAUGUGUCCAACGAACUGCUGGAAGAAGCCUUUUCUGUGUUUGGCCAGGUAGAGAGGGCUGUAGUCAUUGUGGAUGAUCGAGGAAGGCCCUCAGGAAAAGGCAUUGUUGAGUUCUCAGGGAAGCCAGCUGCUCGGAAAGCUCUGGACAGAUGCAGUGAAGGCUCCUUCCUGCUAACCACAUUUCCUCGUCCUGUGACUGUGGAGCCCAUGGACCAGUUAGAUGAUGAAGAGGGACUUCCAGAGAAGCUGGUUAUAAAAAACCAGCAAUUUCACAAGGAACGAGAGCAGCCACCCAGAUUUGCACAGCCUGGCUCCUUUGAGUAUGAAUAUGCCAUGCGCUGGAAGGCACUCAUUGAGAUGGAGAAGCAGCAGCAGGACCAAGUGGACCGCAACAUCAAGGAGGCUCGUGAGAAGCUGGAGAUGGAGAUGGAAGCUGCACGCCAUGAGCACCAGGUCAUGCUAAUGAGACAGGAUUUGAUGAGGCGCCAAGAAGAACUUCGGAGGAUGGAAGAGCUGCACAACCAAGAGGUGCAAAAACGAAAGCAACUGGAGCUCAGGCAGGAGGAAGAGCGCAGGCGCCGUGAAGAAGAGAUGCGGCGGCAGCAAGAAGAAAUGAUGCGGCGACAGCAGGAAGGAUUCAAGGGAACCUUCCCUGAUGCGAGAGAGCAGGAGAUUCGGAUGGGUCAGAUGGCUAUGGGAGGUGCUAUGGGCAUAAACAACAGAGGUGCCAUGCCCCCUGCUCCUGUGCCAGCUGGUACCCCAGCUCCUCCAGGACCUGCCACUAUGAUGCCGGAUGGAACUUUGGGAUUGACCCCACCAACAACUGAACGCUUUGGUCAGGCUGCUACAAUGGAAGGAAUUGGGGCAAUUGGUGGAACUCCUCCUGCAUUCAACCGUGCAGCUCCUGGAGCUGAAUUUGCCCCAAACAAACGUCGCCGAUACUAAUAAGUUGCAGUGUCUAGUUUCUCAAAACCCUUAAAAGAAGGACCCUUUUUGGACUAGCCAGAAUUCUACCCUGGAAAAGUGUUAGGGAUUCCUUCCAAUAGUUAGAUCUACCCUGCCUGUACUACUCUAGGGAGUAUGCUGGAGGCAGAGGGCAAGGGAGGGGUGGUAUUAAACAAGUCAAUUCUGUGUGGUAUAUUGUUUAAUCAGUUCUGUGUGGUGCAUUCCUGAAGUCUCUAAUGUGACUGUUGAGGGCCUGGGGAAACCAUGGCAAAGUGGAUCCAGUUAGAGCCCAUUAAUCUUGAUCAUUCCGGUUUUUUUUUUUUUUGUCCAUCUUGUUUCAUUUGCUUGCCCCGCCCCCGAGACGGAGUCUUACUCUGUCGCCCAGGCUGGAGUGUAGUGGCAUGAUCUCGGCUCACUGCAAUCUCUGCCUCCCGGGUUCAAGCUUGUCCAGGUUGAUCUUGAACUCCUGACCUCGUGAUCUACCCACCUCGGCCUCCCAAAAUGCUGGGAUUACAGGGGUGAGCCACCGUGCCCAACCUCACUUGCUUCUUAUCCUUACACUCCCCCAGCCCCAGAGAAACUGCCACAUACACCACAAAAACCAAACAUCCCCCAAUGACCUUAGCCCCAUUGCUCCAUUCACUCCCAGGUGAGAAUUCAGGCAAACGUCCACAAAGGUCACAGGCAGCGUACAUACGGUUCUGUUAUACCCCAUAUAUUACCCCUUCAUGUCCUAAAGAAGACAUUUUCUCUUAGAGAUUUUCAUUUUAGUGUAUCUUUAAAAAAAAAUCUUGUGUUAACUUGCCUCCAUCUUUUUCUUGGGUGAGGACACCCAGGAAUGACCCUUUUGUGUCUAUGAUGUUGCUGUUCACAGCUUUUCUUGAUAGGCCUAGUACAAUCUUGGGAACAGGGUUACUGUAUACUGAAGGUCUGACAGUAGCUCUUAGACUCGCCUAUCUUAGGUAGUCAUGCUGUGCAUUUUUUUUUUCAUUGGUGUACUGUGUUUGAUUUGUCUCAUAUAUUUGGAGUUUUUCUGAAAAAUGGAGCAGUAAUGCAGCAUCAACCUAUUAAAAUACAUUUUAAGCCUUUUAA